AGCGGCAGAGCGGAGCGGAGCUGUGAGGCGCCAGUGCGGAGCGGGCGGGCGGGCGGGCGGCGUGAGGCGGAGCGCGGGCGGCCGGCGAAACUCCAAGGGCGGACCGCGGCAGGGAGCGAUCGGCCUCGGGCUGCGGGAGCCGGAGACCGCGGCGGCGGCGGCUGCUGCAGCUGCAGGAGGAGCCCAGGGAACACCGCCCCUGCCUGUGCUCUGCCUCGGGCCAUCGCUCCUCCCCAGGGCCCAGUGCGGACUCGCCUCCGUGAAGUGUCACACCAUGUCUGACCGGAAGGCAGUGAUCAAGAACGCAGACAUGUCUGAGGACAUGCAACAGGAUGCCGUUGACUGCGCCACGCAGGCCAUGGAGAAGUACAAUAUAGAGAAGGACAUUGCUGCCUAUAUCAAGAAGGAAUUUGACAAGAAAUAUAACCCUACCUGGCAUUGUAUCGUGGGCCGAAAUUUUGGCAGCUACGUCACACACGAGACAAAGCACUUCAUCUAUUUUUACUUGGGUCAAGUUGCAAUCCUCCUCUUCAAGUCAGGCUAGGUGGCCAUGGUGAAGGUGUCAGUGGCGGCGGCAGCGAUGGCAAGCAGGCGGCGUUGCUGGGACUGUUUUGCACUGGAGCCAGCAUCAGGAUGUCCUCUCCAAUGGCUGUGCUACUGCAUGGACUGUAUACUCGAUUUCAUGUGUAUGUCGCAGUAAACAAAACCAAACCUCUUUCUGUUUAGUUGCCUGGGGGAAGAAGGCUGCUUUAUGUUUAUUUUUCAAGACUUUAAAAAUAUUUUUUGGUUGUAUUGCACUAGGAAAUCUCUCCCACCUCUCCCUUUUCUCUUUCUUUCCCUAUACAAAAUAAAAGGCCCACCAUAGAGACUAGGCGGCCGAAAGACUAGGAGGGCUGAGGAAAAGAAAUAGGUCUCUGGAGGUGGAACUAAAACUGUGCAGCUGCCUCUUCCUGGCGGUGGAUGCUGCUUUGGGAGGGCCAGGGAGGCUGCAGGGGGACAGUGUUGGGAUUGUCAAGGAAAAAGGGGUAGGAAGGAAGGUGGAGGGAUUGAUCUAGUACCAGGGAGAAUAUUCCACUGAACUGUGAUUCUAUGGCUUGGGGCGGAGGGUGGGGUGGGGAUGCCUUCUUUAGGGGCCCUGAGAUGUGUUUGUCUGUGGUGUGUGGGAGUGGGGAGCAGAUUUGUCUUGCUGUCUUUGUCAGAAUUUCUAAGUAAGGGCUGUGUCUUUGUGGAUUACCUUCUUUUGUUCUUCCUGCCAGAGAUCAUGACAGGAGGAUGCUGGGGUAGGAUUAGCUUGAAUCUUUUUUUUCUUUACAUUUUUCUCCUGUCUGCUCCCUGCUUAGCCCUCAGUUUCCUCAUUCCUCUGGAGUUCUCUUAGAGCAGCCCCUGUUGUUAGUUGGCUGGCAAGGGAAUUUCUGGUGACUGUAGUUCCUUAGUUAGGUCUUAGCAAUCAAACCAAAUUGAUGUCUCCCUUGACUCUUCUGUGUAUAUGUGUGAAUAUGUGUGUAUAUGUGUGUGUAUGUGUGUGUGGGGUUUGGGGUAGAAGGGAGGGAGGGGGCAGGACAGUGUGGAAUCUCUAGGGUGUAUGGGUAGGUAGGGGGCACAGUUAGUUCUAAGUGGGCUUUUAUGCUAAAAGCCUCUGGGGAUAUCUGUUUUGAAAAUAAAGAUAGGUGUCCCCUCCUUGCUGUCAUCUAGCCCAGACACUCUGCUUGCUCUCUGGCUGUCUGCUCCCUGGGAAGGCUUUAGGAGGACCACCCAGGACAGGAUGACCAUGCUGCCAUCUGCUCUGGAGCUGGGUCUCAGUGCAGAGGGACAGUGACUGUGGAUGGUUGCAGUCUCUGGUGGGAGGUGAGGAUAGAAGUGAUAAAGAGCUAAGAGGAGCUUCUGGGAGCCUUGGAGGAGGUCAGUCUUGCAGUGGUGAAGCCAGGACAUAGGAGAUGGAGCAGGGCUGUGAGAGGAGGAGAUUCUGAGGAGGAUGCAGGGGAAAUCUUGUCUGUUAAUGAAAUAGGAGUGGGGUGGGGUUUGGGGUGGGGUGGUCAUUGCCGUUUGAGCUGCUGAUUUUCAUGAGUCGCCUUCAAAACUCUCGUGUAGGGUUGACAAUGUGGGGGGGUGGGGGAUCCAGCUUAUUCUUUUAUUUUCAAGUCCAUUCUUGGGGCUGGUGGGGAGGCAGGAGAAUACCCCUCCCUAAGCCCUUAGUGUGUGCCGAGCUUGCUUUGUGAUGUUGGCAGGGGAGGGGAGACCUGGGUGGUGACUGAGUUCCCUUUAUCAAACCCUUCAGUGGGCACAAAAUUGAGUGCUUGAUUUUAGGUUUUAUUUUUUUAUGAAUGUCCAAAUCUGUGUUUCCCCCUGCCCUCCCAGACUGUGUGGCCAGUUGAAAGUGUCUGGUUUGUGUUCAUCUCUCCCUCAUUUCUGGAGCAGGGCCUGAGACCCUGCCACAUCUCCUAUGCUCUGCAUCCACGCCUCUUUUGGACAUUAAAGGUUGAUUGAUGCACCUCUGCACUGUUUGGGUCUCUUUGGGGAUGAGGGGUUGGCAUGGUGGCAGUGGUGCCACACAGUGGGUGAGGGUGGAGAGUCUCCAGGGUGGAAUAGAAUGGGGACUGAAGGGAAGACCAGCCACUAGAUACUGAUUGGCCUGUAGCAGCACUUAUUUGUGCCUAGGCUUAUGCCCCUUAAGUAGAGGAAAACUAACCAGCAGCACUCACCCUUAAGGGCUCCUGGGUUCUGCCUUCCUUGGUGGUGAUGGCCAGGUGAAUCAUAUUUUGUGUCUUUGGGAUAGUAACUGCUACCUUCCCAGCUGCCGUCAUGGACCUGCCUGAGCUUUGCUGCUUCAACUUUUGCCCAAAGCUCUUAUCUUUCAUACUCCUCCCUUCUCGGCUUUCCUGAACCUGGAGACUAUUUAGCAAAGGGUCUGGCCACUCAGAAAUGGAAAGCUGGGGAUAUUUAGAAAGAUGGCACCUCUUUUGGUGGAACCUAAGUGAUUCUCUGAAUCCUCUGUUGCCCAGACACACAACUCGAGAAAUCAGCAGUGCCAAGACUUCUGAGAGUGUCUGCCCACCCCUGACUCCACCAUCGUGUGACUGCAAUUCUCUUGGAGGUGUUAGGGAGCCAGAGGUGCUUUGCCCUCUUUGUGUUACUAUUUCUUUACUCAAAAAUAUUUAAGAGUUCUUGUAUGCUUGGGCCUAGGAUGCUGUUCACAGAGGAGAAUGAGACAAGUAAGUUCUAGGCUUCUAUGACAUACACAUUCUUAUGUGUAGAGCAGACAUACACACACUGAUCAACUUUUUCCAAUAGUGAUAAAUGUGUUAUCAAGGAAAUGAACUGGGCAAUGAGCUAUUGAGUGUUGGAGGUAGGUAGAUAGGGUUCCUCCAGUUAGGAAGGUGGUUGGCUGAUCUUGGGGAGAAGUUCUACCUCUGGGGCAGUGAGGUCCUAAGGGAUUAAGUUGAGAGACUCUAGAGCCCCAACUUCUGUUACUGCUUUAGCUGUCGUGAGUAAUUUGACAGAGCUGGAGCUUUGGGAGGGAGAGUGAGGCCACAGUUCACAUUUCAUCAGGGAUGAGUGUCUCCAGGGCCAAAGCUCAUCUACUUUCUUCCCUGAUGAAAGAGGCAGUCCAGGUGGCAUCUGUGAACAACACAUUCCUGCACAGGUAGGUGCACAGUGCUCAUCUGGAAGACUAAUCCUGCAGGGCUUCCUGGAGGAGAUGAGCCUCCACUUUUCGGGGCCCAGGAUGGGAAAGUAUGUGAGCAUGUGUCACUGAAGGGACUGUGGAAAGCAGAUGGAAAUUGUGGAAUUCUCUCGGAACAAUGCAGCCAUUAUUAGAACUGUGCCCAUAGGAGCAUCAAUAUCCCUGCUCCUUGUAUCCUGUUCUCCAGUCUUCUGGGGACCCCCUUUGACUGAACCCAACCAAAUGGCAGAUGACAAGGCAGACCCAGGAUGCAGUCUGUAGGGUUCAGUCCCCCUCCCCACUGGGAACAGCAGGAAAGGGCAAGGUGGUGACAAUCUAAGGGAGGCAAAUGGAUAAUAACCAGCAUGGUAGGGAAUCUUCUUUGUUGCUGUGGCACUGUCGAUCUCUGUUCCCUGAACUCUAGUGUCCUCCAGACUAGAUUUAAGGUGUGGUUCCCCGCUAAAUUAUUCUCUCACCUCCUUUCAGUCUUUGCUCAAACAUCCUUUUAUCAGAGAGGCUUUCUGACAUCCUGUGCAAGAUAGCACCUCUCCCCCAUCGCUGUUAUCCUUACCCAGUUUAAUUCCACGUAGCAUCUGCCAACGCUUGACAUAUUUGUUUUUUGUUUACUUUCUGGCCUGUGACAACUAGAAUAUAAGCUCUGUGAGAGCAUUUUUCUCUUAACUGCUUAUCUUCAAGUAAACAGAACAGUGCCUGUCCUGUAGGAAGUGUUUGAUACAUACAGAUUGCUCAAAUGAAAAAAGAAGGGUGCGAGCAAGCCUGGACAGGCCUGGUGCCCCAGGGCAGCCUUGCCUUUUCUGAAGAGAAUGGCUGCCUUAGGCACGGCUCUCCUUGCUGCCCAAGCCUUGCCACCUUGAAAGGCGUGAGAGGGUCACUCCCAGGUGUAUUCAAGCAAGAGUGCCUGAGCCACUCUUGCUUGGCAGUAUGGGAGGAUGAAAUAGUGUGUUCAUAAAGUGCAUUUUAUUUUUAAAGCAUUUCAGUUUAUGUUGCUGAAACCUGAGAGCGCCCCCCUGAGCUAGACUCAGUAAUCAUUAGACACAUUUUUGGAUAAGCAAACUGAAUCAGAGAAGGUGAGUGGCAAAGCCCAUGUAGCUGGUGGCAUUACUAGAACUUAGCACUGUGAUGCACAAAGGCUUAACUGGGUUUGGCAGCAAGGGUCUCAUGGAUACUCUUUAAGAUGUAGGCCCAGAUCUCUUAGUAGUGAAUCCCUGAUGUUCCCUCUCUUGGGGCUCUGGUUUAGCAAGGACAGCGAGGAUACUUUCCUCUCUCCCUCCUCCUUACUCCUCUCUACUAAGGAUUAAGGAGCCACCUCUUCCUCCUUAAGGCCUUUGGGAGAGAUGGGUCUCCUGGUAUUAGAAAGGAGAGCAGACGCCUAGAGUUCUGACCUCUUGGGCCUCCCCUAAACAAAAAGCAUAGCCCCUUCACUACCCUAGUAACAAGUAUGACCUGUUGCCUGUUGAGGUCAGGUGUACCUGUGUGUCUCUCUCUGUGAUGUAUGUGGGCUUGGUGUCCACAUCAAUGUGCGUGAAUACUCCUACCCACAGACUGCUACUGUGCCAAUAUAGAGGUUCAUAAGAAAGAUAAAAGAGAACCAGCAGAACCCCAGGUUCUGCCUCUCCUUCCUCCCUUUGCCCAGAUAAAGGUGUACAGUGUUUGUGGUGAGGCUGCUGGACACUGCUGUUUUGGGCUUUCUAGAGAGAAUGCAAACAUGCAAAAACAGUGUGGUAGUGUAGGCAGAACAAGAUCUAGAAUCAGAAGACCUGGAGUCGAAUCUCAGCUCCAACACCCACUGGAUGAACGUGGACAAGCUGCUUGAUCUCUCAGAUCCUCGAUUUCUUCAUCUGUAAGAUGGAAACAAUAUGUGUCUUUUCUAAGGGGAAAGAUCAAAUGACAUCAUGUAUGUGAAAAUGCUUAGAAAUGGGUGAUGAUGAUGAUGAUGAUACUGAUUAUUAGGGUAUCUAAUAAAGUUGGGGAAAGAACAAAAUCCCCCCCUCACACCCUAUUGCACCACCAGCCUUCUCCCUCCCUGCUCAAUUAUACCCAUGUUAUAGGGAAGGAAAUAGGGAAGAAACUUGUCUAAGGUCACAUGGAUGUUCGCAACAAUUGGGAUGCAGAACUUGAUCUGACUCCCAGGCCAGGUUUGAUUUUGAUUUGCAGUGGCAGAGAGGACUAAUUUUUUACUAGGUUCUGAGCCCUGUACUGAACUCUGGAUUGCCCUGUACUUGGUGGUGGUAUACAGUUCAGCAGUUUUUAGCAUAUACACGAAUUUGUGCAGCCAUAACCACUAUCUAAUUCUAGAACAUUUUUAUCACCCCCAAAAGAAAUCAUGUACCCAUUUGCAGUCACUUGCCAUUCCCUCUUCUCCCCAGCCCUGGGAAACCACUGACCUACCUUAUAUCUCUAUGAAUUUGCCUAAUCUGGACAUUUCAUAUAAAUGCAAUUGUACAUGUGGCCUUUUGUUUCUGGCUUCUUUCACUUAGCAUGUUUUCAAGGUUCAUUUGUGCUGUAGCAUUUAUCAGUACUUUGUUCCUUUUUCUAGCUGAGUAACGUGUGGGUAUAUCACAUUUUGUUUAUUCAUCUGUUGAGGGAUGUUUGGGUUGUUUCUACUUUUUGACUAUUGUGAUUAGUGCUGCUAUGAACAUUGAUGUACAGAUUUUUGUGUAGAUAUGUUUUCAAUUAUCUUGGGGCAUCUUUUAUUUUUAAUGUCAGUUUUCUAUUUUUAAAAAAUCUAGACAGGUUGGCAAAUCAUUUCUGUAAAGAGUCAGUAAAUAUUUUAGCCUUUGUGGUCCAUGACAUUAGGUAUACAGAUUACAAUUUCUGAACUCUGCCAUUCCAGUGUGAGAGCAGCCAUAGAUAAUAUGUAAACAAAUGAGCAUGGCUAUGUUCCAAUAAAACUUUUAAAAAGCAGGGGACAGAUUGGGCCUGUGGACCAUAGUAUACCAACCCUUAAUCUAAAUGACACAUUCACAUGAUACAUUAUUCUAAAGGCACAAAAAGCAAAAAUUCUCCCUCCCACCUCUGUCUUCCAGCUACGGGGUUACCUUCCUUGAAGCAGUUAAUGUUAUGAGAUUUUGUGUCUCCUUUUAGACACAGUUAAUAAUGAGCAUUAAAGUGGCUAUAUACUAUUCCAA